ACUUUAAAAGUUUACUCGGGCCGGGACGCAGGGCAAAGCGAGCCAUGGCUGUCUACGUCGGGAUGCUGCGCCUGGGGAGGCUGUGCGCCGGGAGCUCGGGGGUGCUGGGGGCCCGGGCCGCCCUCUCUCGGAGUUGGCAGGAAGCCAGGUUGCAGGGUGUCCGCUUCCUCAGUGCAAGGGGUGGGAUGGAAGCUGGCAGGCAGAGGAUUUCAGUUCCCAGUAGCUUCACUGCCUCUGCAGCAGCACAUUCCAGAGAGGUGGAUCGCAUGGUCUCCACGCCCAUCGGAGGCCUCAGCUACGUUCAGGGGUGCACCAAAAAGCAUCUUAACAGCAAGACUGUGGGCCAGUGCCUGGAGACCACAGCACAGAGGGUCCCAGAACGAGAGGCCUUGGUCGUCCUCCAUGAAGACGUCAGGUUGACCUUUGCCCAACUCAAGGAGGAGGUGGACAAAGCUGCUUCUGGCCUCCUGAGCAUUGGCCUCUGCAAAGGUGACCGGCUGGGCAUGUGGGGACCUAACUCCUAUGCAUGGGUGCUCAUGCAGUUGGCCACCGCCCAGGCGGGCAUCAUUCUGGUGUCUGUGAACCCAGCCUACCAGGCUAUGGAACUGGAGUAUGUCCUCAAGAAGGUGGGCUGCAAGGCCCUUGUGUUCCCCAAGCAAUUCAAGACCCAGCAAUACUACAACGUCCUGAAGCAGAUCUGUCCAGAAGUGGAGAAUGCCCAGCCAGGGGCCUUGAAGAGUCAGAGGCUCCCAGAUCUGACCACAGUCAUCUCGGUGGAUGCCCCUUUGCCGGGGACCCUGCUCCUGGAUGAAGUGGUGGCGGCUGGCAGCACACGGCAGCAUCUGGACCAGCUCCAAUACAACCAGCAGUUCCUGUCCUGCCAUGACCCCAUCAACAUCCAGUUCACCUCGGGGACAACAGGCAGCCCCAAGGGGGCCACCCUCUCCCACUACAACAUUGUCAACAACUCCAACAUUUUAGGAGAGCGCCUGAAACUGCAUGAGAAGACACCAGAGCAGUUGCGGAUGAUCCUGCCCAACCCCCUGUACCAUUGCCUGGGUUCCGUGGCAGGCACAAUGAUGUGUCUGAUGUACGGUGCCACCCUCAUCCUGGCCUCUCCCAUCUUCAAUGGCAAGAAGGCACUGGAGGCCAUCAGCAGAGAGAGAGGCACCUUCCUGUAUGGUACCCCCACGAUGUUCGUGGACAUUCUGAACCAGCCAGACUUCUCCAGUUAUGACAUCUCGACCAUGUGUGGAGGUGUCAUUGCUGGGUCCCCUGCACCUCCAGAGUUGAUCCGAGCCAUCAUCAACAAGAUAAAUAUGAAGGACCUGGUGGUUGCUUAUGGAACCACAGAGAACAGUCCCGUGACAUUCGCGCACUUCCCUGAGGACACUGUGGAGCAGAAGGCAGAAAGCGUGGGCAGAAUUAUGCCUCACACGGAGGCCCGGAUCAUGAACAUGGAGGCAGGGACGCUGGCAAAGCUGAACACGCCCGGGGAGCUGUGCAUCCGAGGGUACUGCGUCAUGCUGGGCUACUGGGGUGAGCCUCAGAAGACAGAGGAAGCAGUGGAUCAGGACAAGUGGUAUUGGACAGGAGAUGUCGCCACAAUGAAUGAGCAGGGCUUCUGCAAGAUCGUGGGCCGCUCUAAGGAUAUGAUCAUCCGGGGUGGUGAGAACAUCUACCCCGCAGAGCUCGAGGACUUCUUUCACACACACCCGAAGGUGCAGGAAGUGCAGGUGGUGGGAGUGAAGGACGAUCGGAUGGGGGAAGAGAUUUGUGCCUGCAUUCGGCUGAAGGACGGGGAGGAGACCACGGUGGAGGAGAUAAAAGCUUUCUGCAAAGGGAAGAUCUCUCACUUCAAGAUUCCGAAGUACAUCGUGUUUGUCACAAACUACCCCCUCACCAUUUCAGGAAAGAUCCAGAAAUUCAAACUUCGAGAGCAGAUGGAACGACAUCUAAAUCUGUGAAUAAAGCAGCAGGCCUGUCCUGGCCGGUUGGCUUGACUCUCUCCUGUCAGAAUGCAACCUGGCUUUAUGCACCUAGAUGUCCCCAGCACCCAGUUCUGAGCCAGGCACAUCAAAUGUCAAGGAAUUGACUGAACGAACUAAGAGCUCCUGGAUGGGUCCGGGAACUCGCCUGGGCACAAGGUGCCAAAAGGCAGGCAGCCUGCCCAGGCCCUCCCUCCUGUCCAUCCCCCACAUUCCCCUGUCUGUCCUUGUGAUUUGGCAUAAAGAGCUUCUGUUUUCUUUGGC